CCCAGGCCAGCCUACCGGCGACUAGGAUGCUUUCGCUUUCGCUCUCGCUUUCCAAUACUCGGGACUGGGGAAACCGGGAGAAUAGAAGCAGGUGUCCCCAGCGCAGCCAAUCGGCUUCCGAAGUAGGUGAGUUGCUGCCUGAAGAGAAAAGACAAACUCCAGUAUCUUUCAUUCCAUUGGCCAGACGCGCCAUUCCCCAAGUGAGUUCUGUUCUCCAACCAAAGUGCUGGAUUCCAAGGGACUGGAAGGGAAAGUCCCUAAAAAUCACGAGUUCAGGCGUCUGAGACUUGGUGGGAACGGACCUUCCUCUUAGGUGAGUUACUCUUUGGUUCUGGGGCUGACCUGGAGUUUUGCCAGGAUUCAUUGGCCGCAGCAGGAUGCUGGUGGGGACAGGGUAAAUAAAAUCUGCACUCCUGCGGGCUUUUAUUGUUGAAAGGGGCACUGACGCUCUCCCUGGAAACUUAAAAAGAACAGCCAAGUGAACGGAUGUGUCUUUCUUUUGCAGUGCCCAAGCCUGUUCUAAUUUUUAAAAACUGAUGUCUAUUAAGACCCAAUGUUAACUUUAUGAAAAUGGUUCCUAAGGAGAUUCACAUCUCUGUGUCCGAAUUCUGUGUGCAGCAAACAUCAUCUCAAGUGCGUUUUCCCAACUACGCUUCUUUCCAGGAUAAAAUACUCUAAGUGACAAAUGUUGAGUACAUUAUCAGGUAUGUUCACUAUUGUGAGAACUGAAGCCAUCUACACUCACAUAGCUUGCCAACUACAUUAACCUGACUUCUUAUUCCAUUAUUUUCAUCAACAUACAUUUACUAUUUCAAGAAACUUUUGCCAGGGACCGGAAAGUUGCAAAUAUCUUUAUUGCUUAAUCCAGUAUCUUCUUCAAAGAUCCAACCACUCUUCAAUGGAAAACAUCAAAGAACAGUUUACAUUCUAAGACUUUGAACCUUUACCUCAAAAUCCUAGCCUUGUUUUAUCUACCAAUCCUAAACUUUUACCCGUAGCUGACUCAAUUCUAACCAAUUCCCCUCAUUAAAUAUUAGACUUACAAUGGGACUUCAAAAUCUCAAUACAUAUAGCCCAAACUUGCUCUUCCCUCUCUGAGACACCACUUAAAUUCUGUCAAGUUAUUGUUCUCCAUUACCUAAGUGAGCAAGAAACUUAGCUUUGUCUUAUCAACAGGUUGCUUUGAUAUUACUGGGAGCCAACAUUUGACAUUCUUGGAGGCUCCAGCAAGACCUAAUCAACCUCCCAACCCUCAACUCAGAAUCAGUGUGUGCCCUGAAGUCCCUUCAACCUUCUUGAGGCUCUCCCUGAUCUCAAAGGUGGAGAAAGUAGAUCUUGCAUCAGGUUGAACUCCAGUUUCUUUUUGCUCAGUUUUUCAAGCGCUGAGUUUAUUUUGUCCCUAGGCAUAAAGAAAUCUUUCUAGGAACCCCUUUGGUUAUGGGACCAGAUUUUUAAAAGCUUUUUAGGCUUGGUGAAAAAUCUGCCUUAUCACUAGCAACACUACGACUUGUCUCUGUUCUUGUUUUUUGUUGUACUCGUGUAAAAGAAAAGUUCAAGGGAAGAGAACAGGCUCAAGUCUACUUCUCACGCUGGCUCUGGGGAUUAGGAAAUUCAGAAAGUUUUGUUUCAGACUGGCAGUGCUGUCUGAUAUAAACACAGCGUCAAGUACUGCACGCUGUAGCUACCUGAGGUUUAGGCCGGAAGAGGCACGGCUGAUUUAAAAGUGAAAGAAAGUAACCAAUUGGUUCGCAGACAACCUUUUCCCAAAAGGCGGGCGAUUCAAACCCCUAGCCCCACCUGCUCCGUUUCCCGCCCAGCUGGAGCUCUGGAGCCUUUGCUUCCUCAAAUACGAGCGGGAACUGCGUUGAGCGCUGGAUUCCAGGCCGAGUGCUGGCGAGGCGCGCAGUGAGUGAGCACACAGGGCGCUGGGGUGCUCCGCGGGGCGCGGUCACGGGCGCGGCCGCGGCGGGCUCGAGUCCCGGCUGGGAGGAGAAGGAGCUGGGUGUCAGGAAGCCGGGGACUGACAGCGCCACCCAUCUGGGGAGCCGGGAGGACACAGGUUUUAUUUUGGUAGUGCUGCAAGUCCCCUUGUGUGCUGGGGGGAGCGGGGCGGCGUGGUAGGAUUGGAAGAGGCUUAGAGUUGGCCUCGACCCCUGCCCUUGCCCCUGGAAAGGCAGAAAGUGGGGGUUGGGGUGCGGAGAAGCAGGAAGAGAGGGAGAGUGAAGGAGGGGAGGAAAGGGAGAGAGGAAGAGGGAGAGUGAAGGAGGGGAGGAAAGGGAGAGAGGCAGAGAGGGGGAAGGAGAGAGGGAAGGAAGGAGAGAUUGAGAGACAGAGAAAUUCCUAAGGGGAGCUGUCAGGUGGGCUGGACAUGGGCCCCAGGCUGCACUGCUUUAUCCCUUUGCUGUAGGAAGUCAAGCAAGUUCUUUAGGUAAGUAGAACCUUGAUGUCAAGUAUAAAACAGGGGUUGGUAUAGGAUAGCUAAGAGCACUUUAUAUUUUGAUAUAAUCUGAUUUAUCCUGGAUACUGAAAACAAUGUAGGGAGACGGAGGAUAUUGGAGUGUUUUCUUAACCUCUUGCCCCUUUCCACUGUGAUUGCUCAAGUACAUGCAAAAUUAAUGUUUCUUUCUGCCCAUUUUAUUUUCCUUUUUUUGUCUGUGUCUAUUAAUCAUUCCUAAAGCACCCGGAUCCUCUCUCAAACUUCGUAAGAUGAGACAUCAUGAACAGACACAGUGAAUCCCUAGAUUUUCUUAAUAGUUGGGCAACAAGUUCUUGCAUUUAGGGAUGUUGCAACAUAGCCCAGUUCCGCAAUUGUACAUUUUCUAUUUUUUUUCCUAGGUUCUCUGCUGUUUAAAAAGUAUCCCUGUGGUACCAUCUCCAGGGAGAGCAAGGUUGGAGCCUAAGGGGAAAGAUGGGACGCAGGACACCAGCUAAUCUUUUCCUCUGUACAAUUAAUGACAGCUUUGAAGAUACUGCUAUAAUUUGAAAAUUUGAAAUUAGUGUUUCAGCUGAACCAUCCGUUCAUCUUCAAGCCAUCAUGAGCUGUAAGAAGCAGAGGUCACGGAAGCACUCAGUCAAUGAAAAAUGUAAUAUGAAAAUCGAGCACUAUUUUUCUCCGGUCUCUAAAGAGCAACAGAAUAAUUGCAGUACUUCUCUAAUGAGGAUGGAGUCUAGAGGAGACCCAAGAGCCACAACUAAUACCCAGGCUCAAAGAUUCCAUUCACCUAAGAAAAAUCCAGAAGACCAGACCAUGCCCCAAAAUAGGACAAUAUAUGUUACCUUGAAGGUAAACCACAGGAGAAACCAAGAUAUGAAACUUAAGCUCACACAUAGUGAGAAUAGUAGCUUAUAUAUGGCUCUCAACACUCUCCAGGCUGUCAGAAAAGAGAUAGAAACUCACCAAGGCCAAGAAAUGCUUGUGCGUGGCACAGAAGGAAUCAAAGAGUACAUAAACCUUGGAAUGCCCCUCAGUUGUUUCCCUGAAGGUGGCCAGGUGGUCAUUACAUUUUCCCAAAGUAAAAGUAAGCAGAAGGAAGAUAACCACAUAUUUGGCAGGCAGGACAAAGCAUCGACUGAAUGUGUCAAAUUUUACAUUCAUGCAAUUGGAAUUGGGAAGUGUAAAAGAAGGAUUGUUAAAUGUGGGAAGCUUCACAAAAAGGGGCGCAAACUCUGUGUUUAUGCUUUCAAAGGAGAAACCAUCAAGGAUGCACUGUGCAAGGAUGGCAGAUUUCUUUCCUUUCUGGAGAAUGAUGAUUGGAAACUCAUUGAAAACAAUGACACCAUUUUAGAAAGCACCCAGCCAGUUGAUGAAUUAGAAGGCAGAUACUUUCAGGUUGAGGUUGAGAAAAGAAUGGUCCCCAGUGCAGCAGCUUCUCAGAAUCCUGAGUCAGAGAAAAGAAACACCUGUGUGUUGAGAGAACAAAUCGUGGCUCAGUACCCCAGUUUGAAAAGAGAAAGUGAAAAAAUCAUUGAAAACUUCAAGAAAAAAAUGAAAGUAAAAAAUGGGGAAACAUUAUUUGAAUUGCAUAGAACAACGUUUGGGAAAGUAACAAAAAAUUCUUCUUCGAUUAAAGUAGUGAAACUUCUUGUACGUCUCAGUGACUCAGUUGGGUACUUAUUCUGGGACAGUGCAACUACGGGUUACGCCACCUGCUUUGUUUUUAAAGGAUUGUUCAUUUUAACUUGUCGGCAUGUAAUAGAUAGCAUUGUGGGAGACGGAAUAGAGCCAAGUAAGUGGGCAACCAUAAUUGGUCAAUGUGUAAGGGUGACAUUUGGUUAUGAAGAGCUAAAAGACAAGGAAACAAACUACUUUUUUGUUGAACCUUGGUUUGAGAUACAUAAUGAAGAGCUUGACUAUGCUGUCCUGAAACUGAAGGAAAAUGGACAACAAGUACCUAUGGAACUAUAUAAUGGAAUUACUCCUGUGCCACUUAGUGGGUUGAUACAUAUUAUUGGCCAUCCAUAUGGAGAAAAAAAGCAGAUUGAUGCUUGUGCUGUGAUCCCUCAGGGUCAGCGAGCAAAGAAAUGUCAGGAACGUGUUCAGUCUAAAAAAGCAGAAAGUCCAGAGUAUGUCCAUAUGUAUACUCAAAGAAGUUUCCAGAAAAUAGUUCACAACCCUGAUGUGAUUACCUAUGACACUGAAUUUUUCUUUGGGGCUUCCGGCUCCCCUGUGUUUGAUUCAAAAGGUUCAUUGGUGGCCAUGCAUGCUGCUGGCUUUGCUUAUACUUACCAAAAUGAGACUCGUAGUAUCAUUGAGUUUGGCUCUACCAUGGAAUCCAUCCUCCUUGAUAUUAAGCAAAGACAUAAACCAUGGUAUGAAGAAGUAUUUGUAAAUCAGCAGGAUGUAGAAAUGAUGAGUGAUGAGGACUUGUGAGAAUUCAGUCUACUGGAUUUAAGGGAAUGGCUUAUGGAGUUGUUAUUUCAUAGGCAUUGAAAAUGGUUUUCUAAACUCCAAAAUGGUCAUCUUAUCAAUAAUAAUAAUAUUGACCAUUUCCUAUCUGCCAGGCAUUUUUCUAAGCACAUGAAGAAAUUAGUCCUAACAACACUAUGAGAUGGACUAUAACUUGCCCAAAUUUUUUUUUUUUUUUUGAGACUGAGUCUCACUCUGUCGCCUGGGCUGGAGUACAGUGGUGCGAUCUCAGCUCACUGCAACUUCCACCUCCCAGGUUCAAGCGAUUCUUAUGCCUCAGUCUCCUGAGCAGCUGGGAUUACAGGCAAACGCCACCACACCCAGCUAAAUUUUUUUUUUUUUUUUUGUAUUUUUAGUAGAGACAGGGUUUCACCAUGUUGGUCAGGCGGGUCUCGAACUCCUGACCUCGUGAUCCACCUGCCUCGGCCUUCCAAAGUGCUGGGAUUACAAGUUUGAGCCACUGCACCUGGCUAACUUGCCCUAUUUUAAAGUCAAGCAAUGGGAAGAAUAACAAGAUUAUAUAGUAAUCAGUUUCAUGACACUAAAAGUCAUAUAGUCAUAGGGUUUUUUCAUCUUUCAUAUCUUUGCCUAAAUUCAUUUGCUACAGUGCAGGAACCAAAACUUGUUCAUCUCAUGAUUCCCUACAUCUGACAUAAGGAAAGUAAGUGCUCAGAAAAAUGUGCAGGUCAAUAAGUUGCAAAAGUUGGGGCUGCAAUUAAUGCUAACAUAAGAGCUAAAUGCUUGAUUAGAAAUGAUCUCAAAACCUUUUAGAAUUUCCAAAAUCUUCAUAUUACUGAAACUGUCGGAAUAUAUGGGUCUUGAAAUUCAGAAGAUGAUAGUCACUCUUCCCAUAUUUAUAGGCUAUUAAGGCAAGGGAUAUCUUAAACAUCAUAUUACUUUAUUUAGAUUUCUACUACUCCAAUUAUUAAUGUUAUGUAUUUCUCAUUGUUUUACUUCUUCAUGGUAUUAUGAAGACUAUAUAGAUGAUUCAACCAAGCCUGCAAAUCUCCCUCUUGUGGAAUUCCACUGGACCCAAUCUGUUUUCCAUUUCCAUUGCAAUACUACUAAAGCCAUACAAUAUCAAGCACCCUCCCUCUAGGUCCAGGGACUAUCACAGAAGAAGCAGGCAUGUAAGAUUUUAAGGACUGGUUUCGAGGGGUCGAGUGUAGGAAAACAGCCUGUUGCAUUGUAAGAGUGAUGUCAUCUUGAAGAGCAGCUGGCAUGAUGACUGCUGUUUGACUCCUGCAUACCAAGAUAUUCUGCAGCAAUGUCUUUAAACAGUGCCGGUAGUACAGAUAACCCCUCAUAAAGAUGCUUAUCUAACCUCCCCAGUGUUCAGGUGUUUCACAAGAAAGUCUGAGAUAUGACUAGCUACACGUUUUGCCAAAAAUGCUUGUUAUAUAAAGGGUACUUUUGGGAGGGUGAGUGCCGCCAUUUAGUGGCUGCUAGAAACAUUGCUUCUGUUUGUAAGUUCCUAUUAAAUGUUUCUUUCUGAGAAA